CUCUUGCUCCCUCCGUGCCGGGCUGUGGCCGGGCGGCGGCAGGACAUGUCGCGCCCCGAGGCCGGCGGAGGGCGACGCCCCGGCAGCGGCCCCGCUCCGCUCCGGGAGGACUCCCUGGGGGAGUCUCGGCUUCCUGGGCUGCCUGGGGCUGAGGAAGUGGGGGCGGCCUCCGCCUCUCCCUUGUAGCCGCGGUUCCUUCCCUAUCCCGCAGAUGGCUCUGCUUCCACUUCCUGCCGCGGGCCUCCCGCUCGGGACCGUCCACUUCCUCAGUCCUCCGGCCGCGGCUUGGGCAGGGUCAGGGCUGGGAAGUGUUGCAAAAACUUAACUGCCCUCGGAACUUGCACGCGCCGUGAACUGGGCGGUGUUCCUAAAGGGCUUCGGUUUGCUGGUUUUGUUUUGGUCCUGUCUUGCAAAUGAGCAUAAAGUUGUUUCUCCCCCAGCCUCCUCCCCUUUCCUUUCUGAUAGGGGCCAGCGGCGAAGGGGCUUCUAAGGGGAAGCGCCUGGACUGGGCAUCGCCGUCCCGGUUCUUGCCGCCUGUGGGAGUGUGAGGUUAACCGUGCUCGGUGCAGGGUUGCGGGGCGCGGAGCUUGCUGCGUCCACACUGCUUGUGUGAGCAGUGUCCUCUCUGUGCUCAUUUCCAACGAGAAACGUUGGAACUUUGGUGUUCUUAUCAGAAUUUGGAUCAUUGCCAUUUUGUACCUCCUCCUAAAUGGAUACAUCUGGACAUUGUUCCUGCUCUUCAGUGGGUCAUCUGUGUGUCACAGCCUCAGAAGACCAGCGAGAUGGCUGCCAACAAGAGUAAGGGCCAGAGCUCCUUGGCCCUCCACAAGGUGAUCAUGGUUGGCAGCGGAGGCGUUGGCAAGUCAGCCCUGACGCUUCAGUUCAUGUAUGACGAGUUUGUAGAAGACUAUGAACCUACCAAAGCUGACAGUUAUAGAAAGAAAGUGGUUCUUGAUGGGGAAGAAGUUCAGAUAGAUAUUCUGGACACCGCUGGGCAAGAGGACUACGCAGCCAUUCGAGAUAACUACUUUCGGAGUGGGGAAGGGUUUCUUCUUGUGUUCUCAAUCACAGAACAUGAAUCCUUUACAGCAACUGCCGAAUUCAGGGAACAGAUUCUCCGUGUGAAGGCUGAAGAAGAUAAAAUUCCACUGCUCGUCGUGGGAAACAAGUCUGACCUAGAGGAGCGGAGGCAGGUGCCUGUGGAGGAGGCCAGGAGUAAAGCCGAAGAGUGGGGCGUGCAGUACGUGGAGACGUCAGCGAAGACCCGGGCCAACGUGGACAAGGUGUUCUUUGACCUAAUGAGAGAAAUCAGAACAAAGAAGAUGUCAGAAAACAAAGACAAGAAUGGCAAGAAAAGCAGCAAGAACAAGAAAAGUUUUAAAGAAAGAUGUUGCUUACUAUGAGUGUCAAGGUGACGGAUGAAGCCAGCUGCUCCUAAGGACACAGGGCUGGGUUGGUAAAGAGAAGGCUAUGGUUGACUUCUUGCUUGUGCUUCCCACUCUCCCCGACUUCAUUCACUCAAACUUCUUUAAAUGGGGAAAAAUAUUUGUGACUCUGUGGCUGGCAGAAGAAAUAAGCCCAUGCAAGUGGAAGGGCUGCUUUGUCAGGAGGUUGUGGAAUUUCUUUCUUCUCCCCUUCUUCCCUCCCAAAAGCUUAGCUAUGUAUAAAGUGCCACAGAUAGGAAACAGCUGUUAAUUACAAAGAGAAAGAAUUGUCAUAGCAUCUUAUUUUGUUCCUAGUUUUAUAACAUUACCAUCCUUCGUUUUGAACUACAGAUGUUGUAGUGGGUUUUGGAGGAGGGAGUGGAGUAAGAUGCCCUCCCACUUUUAUCAGUUUAGUAGUAGUACUGAGAAAAAUCCCUUCAGCUCUAAGAACACUGAAAAAUCCACCGAUUUUUUGGGUAAGCUUCUUGGCAAUACCCUGUGGAUCUGAAACAGCUAAAAAAAUGAAUUUGAAUUGCGCCAGAUAGGUCAAUACCAAGCUUCUGAUUCCUCCUCACAUAUGAAAAGUGAAAGUUGUGAGUUGUUUUCCUCUUAUUUAAACAUUGGCCUAUUAUAAUCUGUGUUGGUUAUUUUUCUCCUGUAAGCAUCCUGAUUUUUCUGUAGGAACUUUUCUUUGGCAGACCAAGUGAAGACUCAGGAAUGGUGUGCAUUAUAAAUGACACACAUUGCCACUUGUGUAGAUAUUUUUAAGUUCUUUGGCUAAGUCCUCUCCUAACUGCCUGUCCUCUGGUUAGGCCCCUCCCUCUCCACUAGUGGUGAAUGCAUGUGUCUGUCUGAUCAGCAUCACUGCACACGGAGGUCUAGUGAGCCUCUUGCUAAGUGUCACACACACUCUUCCCAAAGACGUGAUGAGUUAAAGUUGUAUUCUGAAAUCAUGAAGCCAGAGCCUGUGCCAGACCUUCUGCUACCUCUCAUAGAAUUGCUCUGUAAUUCUAAAUUUAAAAUUAGAAGUAGAGAGAGAUAAGCCAUCGCCCCUUUGCCUCUGAGAAUUGGCUGCUGUUUCUAAUAUAAUUAUUUUCUAAGAUAGCCAGAUAGUUAGAAAAAGAUUUUCAUUGAUGACAUAUCUUUAAACUUUCUUGCAUCAGUAUUCUAAAUUGAGCAAACUGAAAGAUUUUCAUCAGGAAAGGAGCACUGUGGGAAGAGCCCAGUAUUCACAUUUUUUCCCCAUUUUUCAGAAGCGACAUUUCAUAUAUAGGUGCCAAAAGUGAAUCGGGGUGCGGAGAGUGGGAACCUUUUGAAUUUAUGAUUGUCACAGAGAUGGUAGAAAUUAUGAUCUGACUGGAAAACAAUCCUGUAUCCCCUCCCAAAGAAUCAUGGGCUUUUUUUUUGAAUAAAAAAGCAGACAAAUAGA